GCCACGCAGCCCCAAGCACAGCGGGCGCUUAAGUGAGAGGGCAAGCGGAACGCUGGUGUCUCCUGAGGGUGACUAAAAGGAUGGGGGCAAUAGGGGAGGGGUGUGGUCCCGGUUACCGGAUCUUUACAGGGCUUCUUGCAUGUUUCACUGCACCGCGUGCACCCUAUAGCUGUCCUGUAUAUCCCAGAUACUCCAGUGCUGGGAUGUGGCUGAGGCUAUCCAGCAAACCUCGGCAUGAGCGUCUCGGACACCCCACAUUAUCCCCCUGAGCUGGAGAGUGUCUCUCAUCCCGUCCAGAGGGACUGCCUUGGACUCCUUGUGCACGCCCAGAGAACCCCUUCCUGGCCUCCCUCCCCCGACGAGGAUCCCAGAUUGCCUUCCUUUCCUCUGGAGGAGCCUGGUUCCAGGCCCCUGGUCCCAAGGAACCUUCCCUUUCCAGCCUUGUCCCUAGAGGAAGAAGAGGAAGAGGAAGAAGAUGAAGAUGCGGCAGAGCCCGAGUGGCUGCGCAGCGAGGAGCAUCCGAGCCAGUUUUUCGCCGAGGCCCAGCGGCUGCGGGAGCAGAGACUGUUGCUGGACGAAGAGGUGUCAGUCGCGGGGCGGGUAUACGGGGUGCAUCGGGUGAUCCUGGCCGCAAUCAGCAGCCUCUUCCGAGACAGGCUGCUGGGCGGCGGAGGUCCGCGGCCCCCCUUCAGCCUCGAGGUGUCCCCAGGGGGCUGGGAGGCCGUGCUGACCUUUGCCUAUGAGGGGGUGCUGGGCCCCGCCUCGCAGGGGGAUGUGCUGGCCGCAGCAGAGGCGCUGGGAGCGCCCCGGGUGAAGGCUGCUGCCCAGCAGACAUGCGAGAGGGCUGGAAAUGCCAGGGAAGAUGUAAAGAAGCCCAGCCAGGCAGAGGAGCUGAGGGAGAACCUGCGCGGAAUCGAGCUCCUCUACCGAGAGGGCGUCGGGUGUGACUUGAAGCUGGAGGCAGGCGGCUGCCAGCUGUCGGUGCACCGAGCCGCCCUGGCCUGUGGCAGUGAGUUCUUUGGGGCCAUGCUCCUGAGCGGGAUGAGGGAAUCCCAGGGCACAGAGGUAUCUCUGCGGACGAUCUCCACCCAGGACCUGCGACUCCUCGUCUCUUUUGCUUACUCCGGAGUUGUGCGGGCAAGGUGGCCAGGGCUACUGAGAGCUGCCCAGGCUGCUCUGCAGUACCAGAGCUCUUCCUGCUUGGAUUUGUGUCAGAAAGGCUUGGCACGGGGCCUCAGCCCUGCCCGUUGCCUGGCCCUGUUCCCCAUGGCGGAAGCCCCUGGGUUGGAGAGGCUCUGGAGCAAAGCCCGUCACUACCUCCUCACCCACCUGCCUGCUGUAGCCUUGUGUCCUGCUUUCCCUUCUUUACCAGCUGCCUGCUUGGCUGAGCUCCUGGAUAGUGAUGAGCUCCAUGUGCAGGAGGAGUUUGAGGCCUUUGUGGCUGCACGGUGUUGGCUGGCUGCCAACCCCGAGACCCAGGAGUCAGAGGCCAAGGCCCUGCUGCGAUGUGUCCGCUUUGGCCGCAUGUCCACCAGGGAGUUGCGGAGGGUGCGGGCAGCCGGGCUACUUCCACCCCUGACCCCAGAUCUGUUGCACCAGCUGAUGGUAGAGGCUGAUGUUCCAGGCCAAGAGAGACGGAGGGAGCCUGACCGGGCACUGGUAGUGAUUGGCGGGGAUGGGCUCAGACCAGACAUGGCCCUAAGACAACCAUCCCGAGCAGUGUGGUGGGCCCGGGCCUUCCGCUGUGGCGUGGGACUGGUACGAACUGUUGAGUGGGGGCAGCUGCCUGCCCUGCCUGCCCCCGGACGCUUCCGGCAUGGGGCUGCAAGCCUGGCAGGAAGUGAACUCUAUGUGUGUGGGGGACAAGAUUUCUACAGUCACUCCAACACCCUGGCUUCAACUCUCAGGUGGGAGCCCAGUCAAGAGGACUGGGAGGAGAUGGCUCCUUUGUCCCAGGCUCGAAGCCUUUUCUCCUUGGUGGCACUGGAUGGAAAACUUUAUGCCCUGGGUGGAAGACACAAUGAUGUUGCCCUGGACUCUGUGGAGACCUACAACCCUGAGCUCAAUGUCUGGAGGCCAGCACCUGCACUUCCAGCACCAUGUUUUGCCCACGCAGCUGCGAUUUUGGAGGGCCAGUUGUACGUGAGCGGUGGCUGUGGUGGGACUGGCCAAUACCUGGCCUCACUGAUGCACUAUGACCCCAAACUUGAGAAGCCAGGGACGUUUCUGAGCCCUAUGGGGGUACCUCGGGCUGGCCAUGUCAUGGCUGCAUUGGGUGGGAGGUUGUAUGUGGCAGGUGGGCUGGGUGAGACUGAGGACCUGCUAAGCUUUGAGGCCUAUGAACUAAGGACUGAUAGCUGGACUCACCUGGCACCCCUACCCUCCCCCCAUGUGGGGGCUGCAAGUGCUGUGCUGCAGGGGGAGCUACUGGUGCUCGGGGGCUACAGUCACCGUACUUAUGCCCUCUCUCACCUUAUCCAUGCCUACUGUCCUGGCCUGGGCCGAUGGCUCUGCCUGGGAACUCUGCCAAGGCCUCGGGCUGAGAUGCCUGCCUGCAUCCUGACACUGCCCGCUGUGCAGCACAUAGCUUUGGUUCCCACCCCACACCAAACCAAACCUGCUGGGUGAAGAGGGAGCAACAGUGUAUGGGGAGAGGAGGGCAUAAGAAAUAGCCUGAGAGAAGGACAGAGAUUGUGGGGAGUGAAAAGAGGCUUUAUUCUUGGUAGUAUUUUAUUCUCACACUGUGCAUUGUAAACUGCUUUUGUACGUAUGAUCUCCGUUGAGGAAAUGGUGGUUCCAGAACUCCUAGGGAAAACAUAUAGGGAAAGGGGAGGCAGCUGAAUACCCAGGUGAGGAAAGGAGACUCGGGAGCAACUCCACAAGGCUUAGGGAUUCUUAGGGAAAGGGCAUCUAGUUUGAAAGAGAGUUAAGAAGCUUCAGUAGCCAAAGUGUAGAGACCAUGGGAGGACAGUUGGAAAAAUGGUUCUGACCCAUGGAUCAUGGGAAAAAUGUGGAAUGGCCAUCCAUGAAAGAGUUUGAGGAGUGUAGGAGUAAGGACUGUAAAUCGUUCAGCCCUUUUUUUCCUGGAACUUGCUCCUUUCUCCUCUCCCACCCCUGGGAUGCCUAAACCUUCUUAACAAUAUUCUCUCCCGGGUAACUUUGUAGGCCUGGUCUAGCGUUUCCCAGCGAGACACCACAGGCUGCCCCUGAGAACCUCUUGGUUUCCUUCUGAGGCAGAAGCUCCCACAUGGACAUGCACGGCACAGGGGCCUGAGAGGCCUGACGGGCCCCCCAGGGCCAUGUGGCAGGAGUGUUGUGUGGGAAAGAUGAUGGGGGCAGAGGCCAAGGAGGGAGAGGCCCACAGUGGAAAAACAGAUGAUCUGAGGUUUAAGGAGAUGGGGUGGAAGAAGUCAGAAGCCUGUGUGCCUUCUUUCUUUUGGGCAAACUGAGGAAUCAGGAGUGAAAAUGAGACCGUUGUUGCCUGAGGUCUCAAGUGGUGAGAGGAUGUGGGGGGAGAGAAGAGUGAGAAGCAGACAAGACUCAGAAAAGUCAUUUCCCCCUUUCAGUUCCUUUCCCCCAGAGUUAUUUUUAAAUCCAUUUCCCUUUAUCUUGGCCAGGGAAGGUAGUCAGGUGCUUCCUCUUUCUCUCUUCCCCCAUCCUGCUCUCCCCACUGCCUCUCUUUUUUCUUUCUCUUCUUUCUCCCUCACACAGUUAUUAAUUACCUACUGUGUGGCAGGCACUGUAGGAGGCACCAAGAUACAGAGGUCAGAGAGCUCCUGACCAGCAGAUAGACAUAAACAAAUACAAAUUUUGAGUGGACUUACAUGUAUGGACGAGUCUUGCGAGAGCCCAGAGGAUAGAGCAGUGAACUCUGCUCAGGAAGGCUUCUGUUAGGAAAGGUGUCAUCCGAUGGGUGUAUUUUGAACUGGAUCUUAAAGGCUGCCUAGAGUCUCACCCAUUAGAGAAGGGGGAAUGCAUUUGAAACAGAAAGAAGUGGGGCAUGCCAUGCCCUGUUUCUCCAUAGCAAAGAGGAAGUGGGUAUUCCAGAGGCUUUUCAGAUAAUUCUGCUGCUCUUGCCACCUACUCUCUUCUCUGGAGCCUUCCUGAGGAUAAUGGCUUUCACUUAAUGAUUGUGUAUUCCCGCCCUCUAUGACUCACCUCUAUCCUUCCUGUCUGCUCUUUCCAUUUCUGCCUACUGGACAGCUGAGAGCAAAAAAGGGUCAGUUUUUUUGUGUGUGUUUAGGUCAAUUUUCUUUUUCUUUUUUUUUUUUUAAUUUAUUUUAUUUUAUUAUUAUUAUACUUUAAGUUUUAGGGUACAUGUGCCCAAUGUGCAGGUUAGUUACAUAUGUAUACAUGUGCCAUGCUGGUGUGCUGCACCCAUUAACUCGUCAUUUAGCAUUAGGUAUAUCUCCUAAUGCUAUCCUUCCCCCCUCCCCCCACCCCACAACAUUCUCCAGAGUGUGAUGUUCCCCUUCCUGUGUCCACGUGUUCUCAUUGUUCAAUUCCCACCUAUGAGUGAGAACAUGCGGUGUUUGGUUUUUUUGUCCUUGCGAUAGUUUACUGAGAAUGAUGAUUUCCAAUCUCAUCCAUGUCCCUACAAAGGACAUGAACUCAUCAUUUUUUAUGGCUGCAUAGUAUUCCAUGGUGUAUAUGUGCCACAUUUUCUUAAUCCGGUCUAUCAUUGUUGGACAUUUGGGUUGGUUCCAAGUCUUUGCUAUUGUGAAUAGUGAUGCAAUAAACAUAUGUGUGCAUGUGUCUUUAUAGCGGCAUGAUUUAUAUUCCUUUGGGCAUAUACCCAGUAAUGGGAUGGCUGGGUCAAAUGGUAUUUCUAGUUCUAGGUCCCUGAGGAAUCGCCACACUGACUUCCACAAUGGUUGAACUAGUUUACAGUCCCACCAACAGUGUAAAAGUGUUCCUAUUUCUCCACAUCCUCUCCAGCACCUGUUGUCAAUUUUCUUUUUCUUUUUUUUUUUUUUUUUUUUGAGACAGAGUUUUACUCUGUUGCCCAGGCUGGAGUGCAAUGGCGUGAUCUCAGCUCACCGCAAACUCUUCCUCCUGAGUUCAAGUGAUUCUCCUGCCUCAGCCUCCCUGAGUUGCUGGGAUUACAGCUAUUACAUCUGGCUAAUUUUGUAUUUUUAGUAGAGACGGGGUUUCUCCAUGUUGGUCAGGCUGGUCUUGAACUCCCGACCUCAGGUGAUCCACCCACCUCGACCUCCGAAAGUGCUGGGAUUACAGGCGUGAGCCACAAUGCCCGGCCUGUGUAGGUCAGUUUUCUAUUACCAUUGUUUAUUAAGAUUUUCAUGUUUCUAAGGGUGAUGAUGGAGUCUCCCUUGCACCCUUCUUCAUUCUGGCCCCAGAAGUACUUGGCAUGUAUUUUAUUUAUUUAUUUUUAGAUUUCGUUAUUUUAGUAAGAUCUUUUUCUGUAUCUCUAUUUAAGAUAGACUAGGAAUGUAAUUGAAAAUGAGAAGGGGUAAGUAGGAUGUAUAAGAGAAAAGAGAAGGAAGAAUAAAGAACGGGAAGAAGGAAAUUGAAGGAGAUGACAAGCUCUCUGGAUGAACUUCUAUGAACAUUUUUUGUGAUUUGUACCUAAAGGCAGACUUAAAUAAAGGUUUCAUAGUGACUGAA